CUUCCUGGAAGAGGCAACUGAGGCUGAGUUUUGAAUAAUGAGUAAGAAUUAGCCAGGUCAAAGUGUGAUGGGAGUGGAUGAGUGGGUUGAGAAAGAUGUUCCUGUCAGAGGAAACCCUUUGUGCAAAGGCUUGGAGGGUGGGGUGUGUGGAGCAUUUGUUUUGAAAUUGCAGGUGGUUUGGUCAAGCCCAGGAUGGGCAGAACUCACAUCCAAUCUGUCUGGGUGCUGUGUACUUGCUGGGAUAGCUUGGACAGACUAUAUGAUCUUUCUGUGUCCCAUUUUCUCAUCCAUAAAUGGGGAGAAUAUUAGUCCCAGUCUUACGGAGUUGUCAGAAGGACCCCCUUACAAUAAGACACACAGAGUUCUGAGCACAGGGGCAGGCACACAGGGAGCACUAGCAAAUGUCAGCUGUUGGUAUUAGGAGAGCCCGGGGCUGCUAGGUGAUGGGGACAAUCUUCCUCUGGAAGCCAGUGGACACAGGGCAGAGGUGCAGUCAGAUCUGCAUUUCAGAAGGGUCCUCCAGCUGCUGCGUGGAAAGUGUCUAGGAGGGAAAGAUUGGAGGCUACUCCAGAACCAGGUGGAGGGUCCACCUGGAGGGAGAAGCUGGAGGCUGGAGAUGAGAGGACUGAAGGGGCCUGGGCAGUACACAGCAGUUACGAAGGUAGCUCUGGAGCCAGACAGCCUGGUAGGAAUCCCAGCUUUGCCACUUACUCACUGUAGAAUCUUGGCAGGCUCUAGAAUCUUAACUCAGUUUCCUCAUCUGUAAAGUGGGCAUGGCAACAGCACCAGUGCUGUAGAGUUUCUGUGAAUAUGUAUGAGUUAAUCCACGAGAACUGCUCAGAACAUCGAAUUGCUGAGACAGGAUGGCCUGGCAGGGGCUGGUCCUGGCUGCCUGCCUCCUCAUGUUCCCCUCCACCACAGCGGACUGCCUGUCGCGGUGCUCCUUGUGUGCUGUAAAGACCCAGGAUGGUCCCAAACCUAUCAAUCCCCUGAUUUGCUCCCUGCAAUGCCAGGCUGCCCUGCUGCCCUCUGAGGAAUGGGAGAGAUGCCAGAGCUUUCUGUCUUUUUUCACCCCCUCCACCCUUGGGCUCAAUGACAAGGAGGACUUGGGGAGCAAGUCGGUUGGGGAAGGGCCCUACAGUGAGCUGGCCAAGCUCUCUGGGUCAUUCCUGAAGGAGCUGGAGAAAAGCAAGUUUCUCCCAAGUAUCUCAACAAAGGAGAACACUCUGAGCAAGAGCCUGGAGGAGAAGCUCAGGGGUCUCUCUGACGGGUUUAGGGAGGGAGCAGAGUCUGAGCUGAUGAGGGAUGCCCAGCUGAACGAUGGUGCCAUGGAGACUGGCACACUCUAUCUCGCUGAGGAGGACCCCAAGGAGCAGGUCAAACGCUAUGGGGGCUUUUUGCGCAAAUACCCCAAGAGGAGCUCAGAGGUGGCUGGGGAGGGGGACGGGGAUAGCAUGGGCCAUGAGGACCUGUACAAACGCUAUGGGGGCUUCUUGCGGCGCAUUCGUCCCAAGCUCAAGUGGGACAACCAGAAGCGCUAUGGCGGUUUUCUCCGGCGCCAGUUCAAGGUGGUGACUCGGUCUCAGGAAGAUCCGAAUGCUUACUCUGGAGAGCUUUUUGAUGCAUAAGCACCUCUUUUCAUGGAGUAGAGUCAGGAGAAACCCCUGACACCUUUUCAGGUUGGAGUGCAUUCAUUCAUCCUCUUAUAUGUGCCCCUUCCCCAUGCUCAGCUCAGCAUUGUGUACAAAAUAUCCAAGCCCAGCCUAUCUCUCUUCUGCGUGGGAGUAUGUUAUUUCUCUGGGGUCUGUGAUGGGGAAGGGUGGAUGUCCCUUCCCCACAAUAGGCUUAGUGCUUGGCUCAGACACCUAGACUCUAAAACUAUCAGCAGCGGCAGCAGCAGCAGCAGCAGCAGUUUGUGAUCUGUCCUUCCAACCUGUUCACGUGACUCCUCAAUUCCAGGGAACCAGAGCGAUGUGUUCUUUGUACCUGUAGGUCUAUGAUGUCCAAACUUAACAGAUCACAUGCCCCUCUUAGAAGAAAUAUGAGCAUGCUCCCUCAUGCAGAUAGUAUACACAUCAUAAACAAAGAGUAGAACUUUAAAAGAAGGUAAAUAAUCAUACACAGAAAUCCUAACAUUAUAUUCCCAAAUCUCAAAAGAUCUCCUGUGCACCUGACUUUGGAGACGAUGCUUUAGGUAAAAAGCUUAAACAUUGCCUUAUAUUGGAUCAGGAACCCUUACAGUAGAGGGUCCAGUCUUCUAGUGGGUUUAAUGUUUAGUCAGUGUACUCUGAGUCCUCAUUGUUCAGAAAAGCACCUCUUGAAGAACUGACUUCCUGAACUCCCAGUCAUGUUGGUACCCUGGACAGUGCCUAACUCCUUACAGAAGGGAGUGAAAACCUCUUUCGGAAAUGAUUGAGAGCAGCCUCUUGAAUGCUUAAAUGAUCAAGGAGGGAGAAAGGCAAACCAAUUUGUUCUGUGCAACAAACUCAAAAUGUGGACCAGUUCCCUCAGCCCUCAUUAAACUAAUUAAACUGAUGGGUAUCAUGCUUCUACUCCAUGGUGAACUGAAGCAGAGUCAAGCUGAUGAAGUUAAGCACAACCAUGUUCUUGAGCAGCUGAAUUGGCUGCCAAGAGUCCAAGCCAUCUGGCCCAACAUACGCACUGGGCAUUGGGUAAGGGACUCCAGAAGCAGCAGCUAGAAAGAGAAAAAGCCCUCUUCAAUCCCCAUAAUGCUUCUUUCCUCUUAAUGUCUCAAAAUAAAACCAGAAAGAGGAAUAAAAUGAUUAAGUGCUUGAGGCCAAAUGAGUUCCCUUGAUUCAAAUAACCCUGAAUCAGAGGCAGAGACCUCCUGAUGUCUUGGUUUCCAUCAAAGCCCUCCCUGUCUGUCUGUCUCUCUUUUGCUCUCUCAUUCCCAGGCACUCUCUUUUGGUUUGUGGGUCCAGGAGAUGAGGCUGGAUAGGAGAGGAAAAGGCUUGAGUCUGGAUAAUUUGUAUAAGAUGCUGCUGAGCACAUCUCUUCAUGCGCAGUCCCCAGGUAUCUGAUGAUGUUCUGAAAUGGAUAGAUUGUUUUAGAGUUAUUUUGUGUCCUUUAAAAAAAUCCCAUUUAUGCAAUUUACUUGGAAUUUGCUUAGCCUUUAAUAGGCUUGUGUAAUUUCCUGCUCCUCCAGUACAAUAAAUAAAAGAAAGAUGCUGAUGA